CAGCCGGGUGACCCAGGCCGAGGCCGGCAGAAGACAGCCUGAUGCCUUGAAGACUUCCUCUUGCACUUUUGUUGGAGGGUGCUGGUUUGCUAAAAGCAGAGAGUAUUUUUCUUUUUAUUUAUUUUGUUUUUAAUUUUUUAAUUUUAGCUCCAGCUCAGUUGCCCAGACUGGAGAGCAGUGGCCAAUCAUAGCUUACUGCCUCCUGGAACUCCUGGCUCAAUCGAUCCUCCUGGAUAAGCCUCCUCCGGGUACUAUAGCUUCAUGGCGGCUGAAGAGAUGCAUUGGCCUGUCCCUAUGAAGGCCAUUGGUGCCCAGAACCUGCUAACCAUGCCUGGGGGCGUGGCCAAGGCUGGCUACCUGCACAAGAAGGGCGGUACCCAGCUGCAGCUGCUGAAAUGGCCCCUGCGCUUUGUCAUCAUCCACAAACGCUGCGUCUACUACUUCAAGAGUAGCACCUCUGCCUCCCCGCAGGGCGCCUUCUCCCUGAGUGGCUAUAACCGGGUGAUGCGGGCGGCUGAGGAGACCACGUCCAACAACGUUUUCCCCUUCAAGAUCAUCCAUAUCAGCAAGAAGCACCGCACGUGGUUCUUCUCGGCCUCCUCCGAGGAGGAGCGCAAGAGCUGGAUGGCCUUGCUGCGCAGGGAGAUUGGCCACUUCCACGAAAAGAAAGACCUGCCCUUGGACACCAGCGACUCCAGCUCGGACACAGACAGCUUCUACGGCGCAGUUGAGCGGCCUGUGGAUAUCAGCCUUUCCCCGUACCCCACGGACAAUGAAGACUAUGAGCACGACGAUGAGGAUGACUCCUACCUGGAGCCUGACUCCCCGGAGCCCGGAAGGCUUGAGGAUGCCCUGAUGCACCCACCGGCUUACCCACCACCCCCAGUGCCCACGCCCAGGAAGCCAGCCUUCUCUGACAUGCCCCGGGCCCACUCCUUUACCUCCAAGGGCCCCGGUCCCCUACUGCCACCCCCGCCCCCUAAGCACGGCCUCCCAGAUGUUGGCCUGGCUGCUGAGGACUCCAAGAGGGACCCACUGUGCCCGAGGCGGGCUGAGCCUUGCCCCAGGGUACCUGCUACCCCCCGAAGGAUGAGCGAUCCCCCUCUGAGCACCAUGCCCACCGCACCCGGCCUCCGGAAACCCCCUUGCUUCCGGGAGAGUGCCAGCCCCAGCCCGGAGCCCUGGACCCCUGGCCACGGGGCCUGCUCCACUUCCAGUGCUGCCAUCAUGGCCACUGCCACCUCCAGAAACUGUGACAAACUCAAGUCCUUCCACCUGUCCCCCCGAGGACCACCCACAUCUGAGCCCCCACCUGUGCCAGCCAACAAGCCCAAGUUCCUGAAGAUAGCUGAAGAGGACCCCCCAAGGGAGGCAGCCAUGCCCGGACUCUUUGUGCCCCCCGUGGCUCCCCGGCCUCCUGCGCUGAAGCUGCCAGUGCCUGAGGCCAUGGCGCGGCCCGCAGUCCUGCCCAGGCCAGAGAAGCCGCAGCUCCCGCACCUCCAGCGAUCACCCCCCGAUGGGCAGAGUUUCAGGAGCUUCUCCUUUGAAAAGCCCCGGCAACCCUCACAGGCUGACACUGGCGGGGACGACUCGGACGAGGACUAUGAGAAGGUGCCACUGCCCAACUCGGUCUUCGUCAACACCACGGAGUCCUGCGAAGUGGAAAGGUUGUUCAAGGCUACAAGCCCCCGGGGAGAGCCCCAGGAUGGACUCUACUGCAUCCGGAACUCCUCUACCAAGUCGGGGAAGGUCCUGGUUGUGUGGGACGAAACCUCUAACAAAGUGAGGAACUAUCGCAUUUUUGAGAAGGACUCUAAGUUCUACCUGGAGGGCGAGGUCCUGUUUGUGAGUGUGGGCAGCAUGGUGGAGCACUACCACACCCACGUGCUGCCCAGCCACCAGAGCCUGCUGCUGCGGCACCCCUACGGCUACACUGGGCCUAGGUGAUGGCAGUCCAUGUGGCUGCCAGGCCAAGGCAGUCACAGGGGCCCUGACCCCAGGCCACACAGACGGACAUGGGCCCACAUGGGAGGGUGAGCAGGAGCAAGGCUGUGCUUGCCUAGGGCCUCUGUGAUGGACAUCUCGUAGGACCCAGCCAGUCUCAUCCAGCAGGUUGGGUUCUAGGGCUGAACCAGGCGCCAGGCUCCAGAGGACGAAGGGACUCUGUUGCCCCACACUAACUUGCCCUGUCCCAAUCCCAGAAACCCAGGACCAAGCUGUGCCUGGGCUCCAAGGACAGGAACACUGGUCCCCCCAUCACACUCACCCCUAAGUGGGCUGGGAGCCAGGCAGGGCCAGGGCAGCUGGGUGGGGGCCGGGGCUGGCCCUGGGACCCCCAGGAACGCUAAGACACAGGCUCCAGUAGGGGCUGUUGCCUCCAAUAAAGCAGCAGUGAGCUUUGCCUUGGUGGCUGGGGCUUGAUUGGGAAGGAGGGGAUUACCAGCUUACUGGGUGCCCAUGCUGAUGUCUAAGUGGUGACCGCAGCAGUACCCGGGAACCCCAACAGUUGGUUGUCUUGUCUUCCAGGGUGCAGGUCACUGAGUGACUUCCCCAGGGUGCACAGCGAGUAACAGAUCAGGACCCAAACUUGGGCAGUCUGGGCUGGGAGCCCACACCCCACUCACCAGUUCUGCUGCCUCAGGUCAGGCCAGGGCAGUGCUGCUGCAGAGCUAGAAGGCCCUGCAGCUACAGCUGCUUCAUUCCCUGCAUUAGUGCCUGGUUACUGGGUACCUCCUGAGUGGCUGUCCCCGUUCCAGAACUUGCAUACACUGAGCGGGCUACAGAGCUAGAAGGCCCUGCAGCUACAGCUGCUUCAUUCCCUGCAUUAGCGAGCAGUUAUUGGGUACCUCCUGCAUGCCUGGUCCCAUUCCAGACAGGGGCCUCUGGCCUGGCUGAGUUCACAGCCCAGUCUGGGGACAGCUGGGUAUGAGGUGCUUACGGCACAGUGUCCAGGGCAGCUGGGUGUGCAGGGACUGGGGGCUCCCGGAAGAUUUUUUGGAGGAAGUAACAGCUACGAUGGGAUGGGAACAGUGGACCCUAAGCAGGCCAAGGGUGCGUAGGGACGGUGGUACCCAGAUGCCCAAGUCUUCCAGGCAAUACCUGGCUCAGGCCCAGCCCCAAUCCAUCCCCUUACUUUCUGCCAUGGAGUUCCAGCAGGUCACUCUCCCUGGCACACCUUCCAGGCUGGAUUUUUAAUGAAACAGACUCAGGGAGGUAGGGGCUGGCAGGGACCCUAGAAUCCUUGUGAUUUUUCUUAGCACCUUAUGUCAGGGAAACCUAAACUGAGGUCAGCACUUGGGCCCACUGACAGUGACUGACUGGGGGAGAAGGUCCUGCAGCCCCCUUCCCCUGGGUGUGUUCUGGGGACCUGUGGUUUGCUGGCGGAAACAAGUGAUGAGGCUGGUUAGCGGAUGUGGGAGGCUGUGACCCCAGGGGGCCAUAGGGUGCGGUGGAACUGCAGGCCCUGCAGAUGACGGCAGCCAGCUGCUUCCAGGAACCAGGUGUCCAAGGCCACCUCUGCAGGGGUUUCCUCUUCAGCCUGCCUGGGGUGAGAGGUCAGUGCACCACAGCCGAGGCUGGAGCACAGGGAGCUUCUGUUGUUCUGAUCUAUCUCUGGAAAACCAGCCAUUCCUCCUCCCUGCAGUCAGAAUUCUUUGCCCUGUCUGACCUGAACUUGCUUAGGGAGUCAUGCCACUCCCCACUGUGGCCAUAGUUUCUCUUCCUGUAAAAUUUUAUUAUUUUAGUUUUUUGUUUUUGAGAUGUAGUCUCACCCUGUCGCCCAGGCUGGAGUGCAAUGCCGUGAUCUCCGCUCACUGCCACCUCCGCCUCUCUAGUUCAAGCGAUUUUCCUGCCUCAGCCUCCCGAGUAGCUGGGAUUCCAGGCGCCCGCCACCACGCCUGGCUAAUUUUUUGUAUUUUUAGUAGAGACGGGAUUUUAUCAUGUUGGCCAGGCUGGUCUCGAACUCCUGACCUCAGGUGAUCUGCCCACCUUGGCCUCCCAAAGUGCUGGGAUUACAGGCAUGAGCCACUGUGCCUGGCCCCUUCCUGUAAAAUUUUUAAAUGGAGAAUUGGGUGCGAGAUGUGGUUUCCAGCCUGGUGCCUGGGGUGCUGAGCUAGUGAGUGGUGCAGUCCAGGACACCUUUGCUUUAUGUCACUUACACGGUCACCUGGAGCCGGCUCAAGUGGCUAAAGCAUCCUGGGGCCCAGAGCCAGGUGAUAGGUCCCUCUGGCCAACUGGACAGUUGAGGCCUGUGGUUACCCGAAGCCCAGCUGGGGCCCUGGUCCAGCCUCGCCUCCCAGACUCUGCACCUGCUAGCACAGCUGUCCACGUCUGUGUGAGCUGCUCUAGGCCGAGGGCCUCAGUUUCAAGAGUGUGUUGGGGUGGGAUGGGGCAGGCCGUGGUCCUCCAGCAUGAAGAAGGAGCCAUGAGGAGUUCCCAUGACCUCCCGAGACUUGCCAUAAGUGUUCUAGUCCACAUAUAAGGGUAGGGUUGGGAUUACCAUUUACUGACCACAUCUGUGAGGUGCCGAGCUGGGUGCUUGACAUCAUUUGCUUGGAGAAGCAGCUGCUAGUAGACCCAUUUUACAGGUGAGAGAACCAAGUCUCACAGAGGCCUGGGUUCAAGUCCCACCUCUGCCACUAACUGGCAUGUGACCCUAUCUAUCCUUCACUGCUCUGAGCCUAGACCCUGGCCCCUGCCUGGCUCCCUGCCAGGCUCCCUGCCACCCCUCACGACCUCUGAUGGUCGUUGUGGGGGUCUCUUGCCUGGCUCCCAGGGCUAGGGUUAGGGCUCUGGAGGUGCUUUCACUCAACCAAGGGGGCCACAGCACUGGGGAGUGAAACUGCCCCGCCUCACCCUGCGUUGCCCUCUGGGUCUGUGAGGGUGGGCUGGCAGGAGGCCUAGGCCUUGCCCUAGGGGCAGUCCUGCUUCCUCAUUUUAUAGAUAGGGAAACUGAGGCUUUGGGAGGACUCACUGACAUACCUACCUUCAAGAUGAGUUCAGGUGGGCUCAGUUCUGGGGCUUGGGAAAAGGGCCCCAGUGGCUUUGGGAAGCACCCCCAGCCCAGGGUGAAACAUGCUUCUUCUCUUCCUGUGGUUCCAUCCGAAGGAUUGUGGUGAGCCCCGUGCCUUCAGUUAAUAAAGAUUUGUAUUGUGAAAAGAUUUUUUCUUUUUUUUUUGGGACACAGUCUCACUCUGUCGCCCAGGCUAGAGUGGAUUGGCGUGAUCUCGGCUCAAUGCAAAUCUCCAGGGUUCAAUCGAUUCUCCUGCCUCACCCUCCCAUGUAGCUGGGAUUACAGCUGCCUGCCAAAUUUUUGUAUUUUUAGUGGAACCGGGGUUUCACCAUGUUGGCCAGGCUGGUCUUGAACUCCUGACCUCAACUGAUCCGCCCACCUUGGCCUCCCAAGUGCUGGGAUUACAGGCGCGAGCCACGGCGCCCAGCCUUGAAAAGAUGUUUUUAGAACCAGAAGAAACCUCGGUUCCCACUGAUCCUUCUGGGCCACGUUGUGCGGAGCUCCCCUGCUGGUUGGGGCUCAGCGCAGCCCCAGGGAGGUGCUUCCUGCACCUCAGGAUGGGCGAGGGUGGGCAUUGGGGGAGAGGGGGACCUGGGACCUGCGGCUUAGUUCCCUGAGGCAGGCAGGGCUUAUUGGGGCCAUUUCAUAGAAAGGCAGAUUGAAGCUCAGCAGGGAAGAGGCUUUUGAGGGUGAUCCAGGCGCUGGAGGGAUGGCCUAGGACACCAGGGUCACACCAGGAACAUGGGAGGGCCGUGCUUGUCUCUAGACGAGGGGAAUGGGGGAAGGGCCACAACCUCUGUUUCUGUGACCCAGCAGCAUCAAGCCCCUCGCUGGGCACCUCGCACACACCCCCUGCCUUAUCUCUGCCUGCACGCCCUGUUCCCUCCACCUAGACUGCCUGCUGAGGGGGCAGUGCCAGGAGGUUGCCUGUCCUUGGGGAAGAGGGGCAGUGACCCUGUGAAGAUGCUUGACAGACAACCCCCACCACCUCAGAAGUGUGUGUGAGUGGUGAACCCUUUUAAGCCAUCUUCCAGCCAUUCUCACUGGAGGGAGAUUUGAUGGGUACAGAGCAGACCCCUACCUGUCUACCCUCCUUCGGACCCCUAGGAAGCUUCGCAGGCCUUCCAGGCUGCCAGACAGCUGCCCUGGCGUUGCCGUCUGCUUCUUCCCUGGCCCCACUCUGAGGGGCUCAGAGCUGAGGCAGAAUCCCUUUUUCAUUCAUUUCCUGCAGAAUAAAACAACAUACAGAAAAGUGAAUAAAACAUAAAUGCACAACCUAACACACUGUUAGGAAGUGAACGAUCUGCAACCACCAUCAGGAAAUAGUUUUGCCAGCACCCAAGUGCCCUCCCCUCACAGUGUCACUUCCGGCCUCUCUGCCCUGGCUUAUGUGAGUCUUGUGUUCUUGUUUUUCUAAAAAGUCUUCAGCACCCAAUUAUGCAGGCAUUGCAGUAUUUUCCUGUUUCUGUGCUUUAUCCCCUUGAAUCAUACAGAUGCAAAUUCUGGCAGCUGGCUUCUUUGGCUCGUUAUUAUGUCUGUGAGAUUUAUUCAUGUUGCUGUGCGUAGUAUAGUUUGUGCAUGUUCAUUGCUAAAAACUUCCAUUGUUUGGCUGUAUCGUAGUUCACAGAUUCAUUUCACUGUCAGUCAAGCUUGUCCAAUGCAUGCAGCCCAGGAUGCCUUUGAAUGUGGCCCAACACAAAUUUGUAAACUUUCUUAAAACAUUAUAAAGAUUUUUGUUUGCGAUUUUUUUUUUUAGCUCAUCAGCUAUAGUUAGUGGUAGUGUAUUUUAUGCGUGACCCGAGACAGUUCUUCCGGUAUGGUCCAUGGAAGCCAAAAGAUUGGACAUGCCUGCUGUAGAUGGACAGUUGGUUUGUUUCUAGUUUGGGGUAACUACACACAAUGCUGCUAGCAACAGUUUUGUCCAUGUCUCUGAUGCACGUGUGUUUUUUGCAAAUGGUGCACAAAUUUUUCUAGGGUUUGUACUCAGGAGUCUGACUCCUGGGUUCUAGGGUAUGAAGAUCUUUCUAAAUAUUGUUCUAGUUUACGUGCCCACCAGCAGUAAAACAGAAUUCCCUUGCCUUCCCAUCCUUGGCAGACAUUUCACUUUUGCCAGUCUGGUGGGGUGUAUAGUUAUGGCCUUAAUUUGCAUUUAGCUAAUUACCAAGGAGAUUGAGCAUAUUUUUAUGUUUUUAUUAACCAUUUUGAUUUUGUCUCCUGUGAAGUGUCUAUCAUCUUUUGCCCAUUUUUUAACUUGUUGUCUUUUUCUUUUUCUUUUCUUUUUUUUUUUUUCUGAGACAGGGUCUCACUCUGUUGCCCUGGCUGGAGUGCAGUGGUGCAAUCUCAGCUCACUGCAGCCUUGAGUCAGGCUCAGGUGAUUCUCUCACCUCAGCCUCCCAAGUAGCUGGGACCACAGGCCCACACCACCAAGCCCAGCUAAUUUUUUGUAUUUUUAAGUAGAGACGGGUUUCAUCAUGUUAUGCAGGCUGCUCUCAAACUCUUGAGCUCAAGCGAUCUGCUGGCCUCAGCCUCCCAAAGUUGGGAUUAUAGGCGUGAGCUACCAGAUUUUUUCUUAUUAAUCUAAUAAUUCUUUGUAUAGUCUUGAUAUUAUCCAUAAUGUGUAUUGCAAAUAUCUUCUCUAACUCUGGCUUGACUGUUUAUGGUGUCCUUUUUUUUUGGGGGGGGUUUUUUGAGACAAGGUCUUGCUCUGUCACCCAGGCUGGAGUGUUAUGGCACAAUCUUGGCUUAUUGCAGCCUCAAUUCCUAGGCUUAAACAGUCCUCCCACCUCAGCCUCCUGAGUAGCCGGAACUACAGUCACGCACUUCCAUGUCCAGAUAAUUUUUUUUUUUUUUUUAGAGAUAGGAUCUUACUAUGCCCCAGCUGGUCUCAAACUCCUAGACUCAAUGAGCCUCCCAUCUUGACCUCCCAAAGUGCUGGGAGUACAGGCAUGAGCCACUGUGCAUGCCAGUUCUUAUUUUUAAUGCAGUUGAAUUGAUCAGUGUUUUCAUUUUGGUUAGUGCUUUUUGUGGCUUAAGAAAUUCUUUCCAGGCUGGGUACAGUGGCUCACACCUGUAAUGCCAGCACUUUGGGGGCAGAGGCAGGAGGAUUACUUGAGCUCAGGAGUUUGAGACCAACCUGGACAACAUGGCGAAACACCAUCUCUACAAAAAAUACAAAAAUUAGCUGGACAUGGUGGUGCGUGCCUGUAGUCCCAGCUACUCAGGUGGCUGGGGUGAGAGGAUUGCUUGAGCCCAGAAGGUCAAGGCUGCAGUGAGCUGUGAUUGUGCCACUGCACUUCAGCCUGUGAGACAGAGUGAGACCCUAUCUCAAAAAAAACCAAAAAAAAAAAAAAAAAAAAGAAAACCACUGAAAUUAUUUCCACUCCAAGGUCAUGAAGAUAGUCUCUUAGAUUAUAUUCUGAAAUCCUUAUAAAUGUAAAUUUCAUAUUUAGGCCUUUAAUUCACCUAGAUUUGGUUUUUUGCAUAUGGUGUGAGGUAAGGAUUCACUUUCAUUUUUUUCUCUCCAUAGGGUUACACACCUGUCCUAUCAUUGUUUGUAAUCUAACUUUCUGCGCCCAUCUGCAAUGCCACCUCUGUCAUAUGUCCACAUAUGACAUAUGUAGAUCUGUUGUUGGAUUCUUUCCUCUGUUCCAUUAGUCUGUCUGUUCUUGUGCCAAUAUCAAGCUGUCUUCAUUAUUAUCAAUUAUGUAUUGAGAUCUGAUAAAGUAAGUCUUUUCCACCUUAUUUUUCUUCUUUGAGAGUGUCUUGACUAUUCUGGCUCUUUGUAUUUUCAUGUAAGGUUUUUCUCCCAUAUAAGUUUUAAAAUCAGCUUGUCAAUUCCAACAACAAUGAUGCACUUGAUAGUUUGGGAAUUUAUUAUAGCUAUCAAUCAGUUUUGGGAAAAUUGACGUCUUUACAAUAUUGAGUUUUCUGAUUCAUGAACAUGGUUUACCUCUCUUUCCAUUUGGGUCUUCUUUAAGGUUUACCAAUAGGAUUUUAUAUUUUUGUCCAUUGUGGUCUUGCUUAUCUUAAGUUUGAUUUGUAAAUAUUUUAUGUUUCUUUUAGUCUAUUGUAAAUUGUGUAUUUUUAAUUUCAUUUUUUUUUUUGUUAAUAGCAUAUAAAACACACCUUGUCUUUUAACUGGAGCAUUUUGUCCAUUGUGUAUUUAAUGUAAUUAAAUCUACCAUCUUAUUUUAUGCUA